AGUCUUCUCUCUCGCUCUCUCCGCUGCUGUAGCCGGACCCUUUGCCUUCGCCACUGCUCAGCGUCUGCACAUCCCUACAAUGGCUAAAACAGCAAUGGCCUACAAGGAAAAAAUGAAGGAGCUGUCCAUGCUGUCACUGAUCUGCUCUUGCUUUUACCCGGAACCUCGCAACAUCAACAUCUAUACUUACGAUGAUAUGGAAGUGAAGCAAAUCAACAAACGUGCCUCUGGCCAGGCUUUUGAGCUGAUCUUGAAGCCACCAUCUCCUAUCUCAGAAGCCCCACGAACUUUAGCUUCUCCAAAGAAGAAAGACCUGUCCCUGGAGGAGAUCCAGAAGAAACUGGAGGCUGCAGAGGAAAGAAGAAAGUCUCAGGAGGCCCAGGUGCUGAAACAAUUGGCAGAGAAGAGGGAACACGAGCGAGAAGUCCUUCAGAAGGCUUUGGAGGAGAACAACAACUUCAGCAAGAUGGCGGAGGAAAAGCUGAUCCUGAAAAUGGAACAAAUUAAGGAAAACCGUGAGGCUAAUCUAGCUGCUAUUAUUGAACGUCUGCAGGAAAAGCUGGUCAAGUUUAUUUCUUCUGAACUAAAAGAAUCUAUAGAGUCUCAAUUUCUGGAGCUUCAGAGGGAAGGAGAGAAGCAAUGAGAGGCAUGCUGCGGAGGUGCGCAGGAACAAGGAACUCCAGGUUGAACUGUCUGGCUGAAGCAAGGGAGGGUCUGGCACGCCCCACCAAUAGUAAAUCCCCCUGCCUAUAUUAUAAUGGAUCAUGCGAUAUCAGGAUGGGGAAUGUAUGACAUGGUUUAAAAAGAACUCAUUAUAAAAAAAAAAAAACAAAAAAAAUCAAAAAUUAAAAAAAAUCAAUGCGGUCUCUUUGCAGAAUGUUUUGCUUGAUGUUUAAAAAAUACCUUGGAUCUUAUUUUGUAAAUACUUACAUUUUUGUUAAAAAAUACAAGUAUUGCAUUAUGCAAGUUAUUUCAUAAUCUUACAUGUCCUGUAACAGGCUUUUGAUGUUGUGUCUUUCCACUCAAAUGAAUUUGCUAGGUCUGUUCUUUUUGAAGCUCCCCAUGUCUAACUCCAUUCCAAAAGAAAAAUGAGGUCAGUAGACAGUCUAUGGUGCUAGAAACCCACCAUUGCCUAAUGACCUAGAAGGCUUUGUUGUCUCUGAGCUUGACUAAGACCAUACCUAGAUCACAGGUAUUAUGACUCCACAUGAACCUUCACAUUUGUUCGCUCAUAAUCUACUUACUGCCUAAAAACUACAAAACCAGGCUAAGAAAUACCACCAGUCAUAGCAUUUACUUCUGCUUCUCCUGGAUUAUGUGCUACAAAUGUGCUUUGGCUUUAGAAAGGGAUGGAUGAGAAGACAGACCUGAGACCAAUCUGGGUAGAAGCAAAAAGUUGAACCUUUUAAAGUGCUGAACACAAAUCCAAAUUCGAAUGGUUCAAGCAGCCGUGAAAUCGCUCUUCAUAAAGUGGGCUUAAUUCUCUAGUUUAAGUUCUUUUGAUGGAAUGAAUUAAUUAAUGUGUCAGGUGGCUUAUUUGUGGAUGCCAUGAUUGAUGAUGUUCAUUUUAAGCUCUUACCUAUAGUACAAGUACAUGAUGCUACUGAAUAUUUUUCCACUUGGAAACUGUGAGCUGGUUGUUGCAUUAAAACACACAUACAAACAAAAUCAAAAACACUGCGGACUUUCACUCAAGCUGGUCUUUCUUCCCCAGUGUAAGGCAAUCCUGCCUACUAACAACACCAACAACAAAACACUCCAUCUGUGAAGCUGACGCAGUUAAGGGGGCUAGGCAGGGCAUUUGUGCCAACUAAGAAUCACCAGAUACCCACCAUAAGUACCUAUCGCAGUUUUGAAGUCGUUUCUCCCCAACUCCCAACUCCUGAAGGUUGCUGCCUGCAUAUUUACUCUUCAUUAGUGCUAUUUUCCUGUAUGUCAUUGUGAGCAAGCUGUGAUUAAUAAAGAAUUGGAGUUCUGUGAACUAA